GUUGCAGUGAGCUGGGAUCACACUACUACACUCCAGCCUGGGUGACAGAGCGAGACUCUGUCUCAAAAAAGAUUUCCAGACUCUGCCUACUGUUCUCUCCUCCCUGACCCCACCUGGGCCCUGCUCCCCGAUCCCUCCCCUUUGGUUAACCCUGGAAGCCUCUUCACUGGCUCCCUGUUCUCCAUCCUCGCCACACAGCCAGAGGGACCUGUGAGCACCUCAGCUGGGUGUCCCACCCCUGCUCAGAGGUCUCCUGUGGCUUCGUCUCAGAGUAAAAGGGUAAAGUGGUCAUCGAGGCCCCUAAGACCCCACCUGAGCUGCUCCACCUUCCUCUUCAGCCCAUCUUUCUGUCUUGUUUGGUCCACCCGACCCGCCUUGACAUUGAAACUCUCCAAACUCCUUCCUGACUCGUGCACUUACAUUGGGUCCCCGCGUGGGUUAUAAGGCGCUGCAACCCUGGCCCGCACAGCGCCUUGGACCCGUUGGACGCCCACCAUGCCGCCCCGAGGGCCAGCCUCUGAGCUGCUGCUGCUGCGGCUGCUCCUGCUGGGGGCGGCCACCGCUGCUCCCUUGGCACCGAGACCCUCCAAGGAGGAGCUGACCCGCUGUCUGGCAGAGGUGGUCACAGAGGUGCUGACCGUGGGCCAGGUCCAGAGAGGACCCUGCACUGCUCUUCUCCACAAGGAGUUGUGCGGGACAGAGCCCCACGGCUGUGCGUCCACCGAGGAGAAAGGCCUGCUGCUUGGGGAUUUCAAGAAGCAGGAGGCUGGGAAGAUGAGGUCCAGCCAGGAGGUGAGGGAUGAGGAAGAGGAGGAGGUAGCAGAGAGGACCCACAAGUCUGAGGUCCAGGAACAAGCCAUCCGCAUGCAAGGGCAUCGCCAGCUCCACCAGGAGGAGGACGAGGAGGAGGAGAAGGAGGAGAGGAAGAGGGGGCCCAUGGAGACCUUUGAGGACCUGUGGCAGCGGCAUCUAGAGAAUGGAGGGGACCUCCAGAAGCGGGUGGCAGAGAAGGCCAGUGACAAAGAGACGGCCCAGUUCCAGGCAGAGGAGAAGGGGGUGCGGGUGCUGGGCGGGGACCGCAGCCUGUGGCAGGGGGCCGAGAGAGGCGGAGGAGAGAGGCGCGAGGACUUGCCCCACCACCACCACCACCACCACCAGCCAGAGGCUGAGCCCAGGCAGGAGAAGGAGGAGGCUUCGGAGAGGGAGGUGAGUAGGGGGAUGAAGGAGGAACACCAACACAGUUUGGAGGCAGGGUUGAUGAUGGUCAGUGGAGUCACAACUCACAGCCACCGGUGUUGGCCCUGCACCACCAGAUCCAUCACUAGUGGAUCACAGUGGCCAAGACUGACACCACGACUGGCUAACAACUUCCGUGCAAGGCCUUUACCUUAUACUUCCACACUACUGUAUGGACUACAGCAACCAAGAUGGCACCAUUGCACAGAAGCAAGCCACCAUCACUAGCAAGUUGGCCACUGUGAAAAGUGGCUGCUGUGCCUACUUCACUAGGUGACAGACAGACACCAUUGCUGGGUCAUGGAAAACAAGAUGUCACCAUGAUUGGUGGCACCAAAAGUGCCGUAACAGGGUGGGCAUGGUGGCUCACACCUGUAAUCCUAGGGAGGGUUAAUCCUUUCAGAGGCCAAGGUGGG